GCCCUCCAGCUGCAGCCCGCGCCGAGCGCGCAGGGCCAGCGAGCGCCGGCGCCUCCAGCAUGGAGUGGGAACUCAACUUGCUGCUCUACCUGGCGCUCUUCUUCUUCCUGCUCUUCUUACUUUUCCUCCUGCUCUUCGUGGUCAUCAAGCAGCUGAAGAACUCCGUGGCCAACACGGCCGGGGCGCUCCAGCCCGGGCGCCUCUCGGUGCACCGCGAGCCUUGGGGCUUCUCCCGAGAGCAAGCGGUGUGACCCGAGUGCGGGCACUGGCGGGAGGGCACCGAGCUGCGCGGGCGCUGGGCUGGGUCUCCGCCUCGAUUCUCCGUCCUCGCGGCCUCCCAGCUUCCAGAGCCGAGCUGCUGCCCUUGACUGGUGCUCAGGGGACCACAGCUGCAAUGACAGUUUGGGCCUGCAAAAAGAAGGCUGGAACAACGGGAGAUGGAAGCUUUCUGCAAAUGCAGCACCACUGGUAUCCAUGAAUUUAACCUGCCCAUCAUUCUUCCUAAACAAGAGACUAUUGAAAAGUCAGGGUGUUCAAAAUGGCUUCAGAUCUUAUCAGGACAAUCUUGGCUGUUGCACUAAUUUCCAAACUUGUAAGUGCAAUGGAUCUGCAGUUCUACUUGGCAAGAUAACCAUUUUAAGUUGAAUGAGAAUGACAUCACACUCACACCUGCAAAAUCUAAAAUGUCUAAUAAAGUAGAUUCCUAUGUCUGAACUUCAAUUUUAGGGCACAGCUGUAGAUGCAGAACUGAUGCCAUCUGGUGCGAUUCUACAGAAUAAGAGAGAAAAUUUACCCAGAGUGUGCCAUGCACUGGCUUUUCUGGGAAUGGCAAGGUGCCAGGAUUUGUUUUUGGUUCGCUUGCAGGGGUGGAAACUUGGAACUAGGUUCCAAGAUGGUCCCCGCAGCACCCCACAAGAAGAAGGAGGAAGCCCACAGAGAAAACGGGGCAUGCCAGUUCAAAUCCACUUCCUUUUAAAGAGCUUCCUCAGCAGCCCAAUAACUUUUGCCUUCAUCUCAUUGGCCAGAACUGUGUCAUUGGCUACUGCUAUCUGCAAGAUUGUCUGAGAAAUGUAGUUUUUGUAGCUGGAUAUAUAACUGCCUUUGACAAAAAUCCAGUUUCUCUUGAUGAAGAAGAAGAUGAUGGUGGAUCUUGGGAGGACAACUAACAUUUUAUGCCCUGGCUACAGAAUACAGUUGCAGAGGAGCAUAAAGUUCAAAAAGAUCAAAACUCUAGUUCCUUCACAACUGUCAAAGCUCCAAGCAGCACUGCUCCCCUCUGACAGAGUGAGCAGAGUGAAGGCAUGUCAGGUGUUCUCACAAAACUCUUGACAGGGCUGACCUCUCUCAGUCAAUAUCCUUGUCCCACAUCAGGAUUUUCUAGAGGGCCCUGGGUACCUGUGCACUUCCUUGGUGGCCGUAACCUCUUUGUGGAGGGUUGGUGUAGGAUAAAGAAUGUUCUAUUACGCUGCUCCCUCAUCUGUAUCAUUUCUCUCCUCUCUAAUUUUCCUGUCAGUUAUAUUUUGGUGGAGUCUGGGUUUGUGUAUUUGAUUCCUAUAGAAAGACCAUCGCUUUCAUGCAUGGAGGAGGGGAAUCUACGCAAAGAAAGGCUACCUUACUCCUUUCUGUGACUCCACCACCAGUCUAGGAAUAUCCUGGGAGAAGAAUUGCCUCUCAAAGCUGCUUCUAUAAGCAGCCUACAUCCUAGCUAAGCAAAGAAGAAACACUUCCCACAUCUAGGGCUGUCUAAAAGAACUUUCUGUGAUGACAGAAAUGUUCUAUAUCUGCAGUGUCCAAUAUGGUAACCAUAUAGGCACAUGUGGCUAGUGAACACUUGAAAUGUGGCUAGUGUGACUGAGGAAGGAAAAUUUAAAUUUUGUUUAAUUGUAAUUAAUUUAAAUUCAGAUAGCCAAAUGGGGCUACUAGCUAUUGUGUUAGAUAGCACGGUAUACUUUAUUCUCUUUCUUGUGUUGUAGAACCAGCUGGGAGAGGUGUGGGUCAGUCAUGGGCUUGGUAUCCCCUGGUCUUCACUAUUCUAGCUUGCCAUUGAAUUUGUCUCCCAGAGGAAAAGAAAGAAUGGUAUUUGGAAUUAAAUUCAAGAUGUUAACUUGACAUCUAUAUAUUGCACAUAUUCCUGUAUAGUGAAUGGAUGACCUCCUGGGAAUAGUUCCUGUGACUGAUUUUAGUGAUAAUUGAUCAUGAAGAAAUGGCAGUACUGCUCCACUUCACCUUCCUAGUGACUAUUAUGUGUUCCUAGUCAGAGUGACUCAGCAGAGAUUAUUUUGUUCUCUUGUGCAAUUUAUUCUGUGUCAUUUUAUUUUUGUAAUAUUGUGGCAGCUAAAUGAUUAUUCUGUGUAUGUUUUUCAAAAUAUUAGGUGGCUUAUAUUUUUUAAAAGGCUAUGAAAUAAAAAUAAACUAUACGUAACACAGUU